GUUCAGAGUCACCCAUCUCAGCAAGCCCAGAAGCAUCUGCAAUAUCUAUGAUGGCCUCGCCCUUUGCUUUACUGAUGGCCCUGGUGGUGCUCAGCUGCAAGUCAAGCUGCUCUCUGGGCUGUGAUCUCCCUGAGACCCACAGCCUGGAUAACAGGAGGACCUUGAUGCUCCUGGCACAAAUGAGCAGAAUCUCUCCUUCCUCCUGUCUGAUGGACAGACAUGACUUUGGAUUUCCCCAGGAGGAGUUUGAUGGCAACCAGUUCCAGAAGGCUCCAGCCAUCUCUGUCCUCCAUGAGCUGAUCCAGCAGAUCUUCAACCUCUUUACCACAAAAGAUUCAUCUGCUGCUUGGGAUGAGGACCUCCUAGACAAAUUCUGCACCGAACUCUACCAGCAGCUGAAUGACUUGGAAGCCUGUGUGAUGCAGGAGGAGAGGGUGGGAGAAACUCCCCUGAUGAAUGCGGACUCCAUCUUGGCUGUGAAGAAAUACUUCCGAAGAAUCACUCUCUAUCUGACAGAGAAGAAAUACAGCCCUUGUGCCUGGGAGGUUGUCAGAGCAGAAAUCAUGAGAUCCCUCUCUUUAUCAACAAACUUGCAAGAAAGAUUAAGGAGGAAGGAAUAACACCUGGUCCAACAUGAAACAAUUCUUAUUGACUCAUAUACCAGGUCACGCUUUCAUGAAUUCUGC